GCCCUAUCAGUGAAGUCAAAGAUUGAAGAGGAACUCUUUCAAACCUUUCAAGUGCCCCCUCCUUUCCUUAAAGUCUUUUAUAGGGGUCCCCUUCUUGGCCAUCUCCAUCCUGUGAGUCAGGACUGAAAGGGCACAGACAGGUCACUGCCAGCAUUGUUGGGGCAAGCCUGCAAGCACGCAUCACUGGGGAUCUGACAUGACAAUGGCCGCCUGCCCCCUCUGAGGGCUACAGGACUUACCCCAGUGGGAAGCAGCUAAGCAGUCAGUGGGCCUGUCUUCUGUGUCCCAGGCUCGUAACAGAGGACAUUCACACGUGAGCAUGCCCAUAGGCAGAUAGGAACAAUUCUCAAGGUCUGACCAGCCGACCUGGACCUGGCCAAGGGUCCUGUCAUCCCUCAUGGCCACCCCGCCAUUCCGGCUGAUAAGGAAGAUGUUUUCCUUCAAGGUGAGCAGAUGGAUGGGGCUUGCCUGCUUCCGGUCCCUGGCGGCAUCCUCUCCCAGUAUUCGCCAGAAGAAACUAAUGCACAAGCUGCAGGAGGAAAAGGCUUUUCGCGAAGAGAUGAAAAUUUUUCGUGAAAAAAUAGAGGACUUCAGGGAAGAGAUGUGGACUUUCCGAGGCAAGAUCCAUGCUUUCCGGGGCCAGAUCCUGGGUUUUUGGGAAGAGGAGAGACCUUUCUGGGAAGAGGAGAAAACCUUCUGGAAAGAGGAAAAAUCCUUCUGGGAAAUGGAAAAGUCUUUCAGGGAGGAAGAGAAAACUUUCUGGAAAAAGUACCGCACUUUCUGGAAGGAGGAUAAGGCCUUCUGGAAAGAGGACAAUGCCUUAUGGGAAAGAGACCGGAACCUUCUUCAGGAGGACAAGGCCCUGUGGGAGGAAGAAAAGGCCCUGUGGGUAGAGGAAAGAGCCCUCCUUGAGGGGGAGAAAGCCCUGUGGGAAGAUAAAACGUCCCUCUGGGAGGAAGAGAAUGCCCUCUGGGAGGAAGAGAGGGCCUUCUGGAUGGAGAACAAUGGCCACAUUGCCGGAGAGCAGAUGCUCGAAGAUGGGCCCCACAACGCCAACAGAGGGCAGCGCUUGCUGGCCUUCUCCCGAGGCAGGGCGUAGCCAGCAUGCAGGUGCAGGGCCCUGUGGUCCAGACUCCCCUGGGUUGGGAUUCAAGUCCAGGGUGAGCCCAUGUGCUGGAGAAAAUACACACUCAUUGGUCUCCUUGCUUUGAAAGAUCCAAUAAAGUCCUGAGGCAAGGUUUGGAAAACCAA